ACUUCCGUCCGGCGCGCGGCGUCCUCCUCCCGCUCGGAAGGUCCCAGGUGUGACACCUUCAGCAGGUCUCAGGGAAGAUGGCAGCCCUAGGGGACAUUCAGGAGUCCCCUUCUGUCCCGUCCCCUGUCAGUCUCUCAUCACCGGGGACACCUGGAACCCAGCACCACGAGCCUCAGCUUCACCUCCAUGGGCAUCAACAUGGCUCCCCUGGCUCCAGCCCUAAGGUGCUCUCCCAGCCGUCCGACCUGGAUCUCCAAGACGUAGAGGAAGUGGAGAUCGGCAGAGACACCUUCUGGCCCGACUCCGAGCCCAAGCCGGAGCAGGCUCCACGCUCUCCUGGCUCUCAGGCCCCUGACGAGGGGGCGGGCGGGGCGCUGCGCAGCCUCCUGAGGAGCCUUCCCCGCAGGGCCCGGUGCAGCGCCGGCUUCGGGCCUGAAUCCAGCGCGGAGCGGCCGGCGGGCCAGCCGCCUGGGGCCGUCCCUUGCGCCCAGCCGCGGGGCGCCUGGCGCGUGACGCUCGUGCAGCAAGCAGCGGCCGGGCCCGAGGGUGCGCCCGAGCGGGCUGCCGAGCUGGGAGUCAACUUCGGUCGGAGCCGGCAGGGCAGCGCGCGGGGGGCCAAGCCGCACAGGUGCGAGGCCUGCGGCAAGAGUUUCAAGUAUAACUCGCUGCUCCUGAAGCACCAGCGCAUCCACACGGGCGAGAAGCCCUACGCCUGCCACGAGUGCGGCAAGCGCUUCCGCGGCUGGUCGGGCUUCAUCCAGCACCACCGCAUCCACACGGGCGAGAAGCCCUACGAGUGCGGCCAGUGCGGCCGCGCCUUCAGCCACAGCUCGCACUUCACGCAGCACCUGCGCAUCCACAACGGCGAGAAGCCCUACAAGUGCGGCGAGUGCGGCCAGGCCUUCAGCCAGAGCUCCAACCUGGUGCGCCACCAGCGGCUGCACACGGGUGAGAAGCCCUACGCCUGCAGCCAGUGCGGCAAGGCCUUCAUCUGGAGCUCCGUGCUCAUCGAGCACCAGCGCAUCCACACUGGCGAGAAGCCCUACGAGUGCUCCGACUGCGGCAAAGCCUUCCGCGGCCGCUCGCACUUCUUCCGGCACCUGCGGACCCACACGGGCGAGAAGCCCUUCGCGUGUGGCGCCUGCGGCAAGGCCUUCGGCCAGAGCUCCCAGCUCAUCCAGCACCAGCGGGUGCACUACCGCGAGUAGCCGGGCGGGGGCUCGGGGCUCGGCCUCCUACCUGCCCCCAACCCACCCUCCACCCCGUCCCCCACGGUGGGCACUGCCCAGCACCGCAUGCCACGUGUCCGGAAUAAAUUCUUUUUGAUUGUUGGAA